GUGGCGAGUGCCGGCCGAAAGCUAGGUCCGGAUUGCACGUGGAGGGCCGCCCGAAGGGCACUCUCGGACAUUAACCCGCAUUCUGUACCAUGGGGCGCAAGUUGGACCCUACGAAGGAGAAGCGGGGGCCAGGCCGAAAGGCCCGGAAGCAGAAGGGUGCCGAGACAGAACUCGUCAGAUUCUUGCCUGCAGUAAGUGACGAAAAUUCCAAGAGGCUGUCUAGUCGUGCUCGAAAGAGGGCAGCCAAGAGGAGAUUGGGCUCUGUUGAAGCCCCUAAGACAAAUAAGUCUCCUGAGGCCAAACCAUUGCCUGGAAAGCUACCAAAAGGAGCUGUCCAGACAGCUGGUAAGAAGGGACCCCAGUCCCUAUUUAAUGCUCCUCGAGGCAAGAAGCGCCCAGCACCUGGCAGUGAUGAGGAAGAGGAGGAGGAAGACUCUGAAGAAGAUGGUAUGGUGAACCACGGGGACCUCUGGGGCUCCGAGGACGAUGCUGAUACGGUAGAUGACUAUGGAGCUGACUCCAACUCUGAGGAUGAGGAGGAAGGUGAAGCGUUGCUGCCCAUUGAAAGAGCUGCUCGGAAGCAGAAGGCCCGGGAAGCUGCUGCUGGGAUCCAGUGGAGUGAAGAGGAGACCGAGGACGAGGAGGAAGAGAAAGAAGUGACCCCUGAGUCAGGCCCCCCAAAGGUGGAAGAGGCAGAUGGGGGCCUGCAGAUCAAUGUGGAUGAGGAACCAUUUGUGCUGCCCCCUGCUGGGGAGAUGGAGCAGGAUGCCCAGGCUCCAGACCUGCAACGAGUUCACAAGCGGAUCCAGGAUAUUGUGGGAAUUCUGCGUGAUUUUGGGGCUCAGCGGGAGGAAGGGCGGUCUCGUUCUGAAUACCUGAACCGGCUCAAGAAGGAUCUGGCCAUUUACUACUCCUAUGGAGACUUCCUGCUUGGCAAGCUCAUGGACCUCUUCCCUCUGUCUGAGCUGGUGGAGUUCUUAGAAGCUAAUGAGGUGCCUCGGCCCGUCACCCUCCGGACCAAUACCUUGAAAACCCGACGCCGAGACCUUGCACAGGCUCUAAUCAAUCGUGGGGUUAACCUGGAUCCCCUGGGCAAGUGGUCAAAGACUGGACUAGUGGUGUAUGAUUCUUCUGUGCCCAUUGGUGCUACCCCCGAGUACCUGGCUGGGCACUACAUGCUGCAGGGAGCCUCCAGCAUGUUGCCCGUCAUGGCCUUGGCACCCCAGGAACAUGAGCGGAUCCUGGACAUGUGUUGUGCCCCUGGAGGAAAGACCAGCUACAUGGCCCAGCUGAUGAAGAACACGGGUGUGAUCCUUGCCAAUGACGCCAAUGCUGAGCGGCUCAAGAGUGUUGUGGGCAACUUGCAUCGGCUGGGAGUCACCAACACCAUUAUCAGCCACUAUGAUGGGCGCCAGUUCCCCAAGGUGGUGGGGGGCUUUGACCGAGUACUGCUGGAUGCUCCCUGCAGUGGCACUGGGGUCAUCUCCAAGGAUCCAGCCGUGAAGACUAACAAGGAUGAGAAGGACAUCCUGCGCUGUGCUCACCUCCAGAAGGAGUUGCUCCUGAGUGCUAUUGACUCUGUCAAUGCGACCUCCAAGACAGGAGGCUACCUGGUUUACUGCACCUGUUCUAUCACAGUAGAAGAGAAUGAGUGGGUGGUAGACUAUGCUCUGAAAAAGAGGAAUGUGCGACUGGUGCCCACGGGCCUAGACUUUGGCCAGGAAGGUUUUACCCGCUUUCGAGAAAGGCGCUUCCACCCCAGUCUGCGUUCUACCCGACGCUUCUACCCUCAUACCCACAAUAUGGAUGGGUUCUUCAUUGCCAAGUUCAAGAAAUUUUCCAAUUCUAUCCCUCAGUCCCAGACAGACGGUGUCUUGCUUUGUCGCUCAGGCUGGACUGCAGUGGUGCAAUCUCAGCUCAUUGCAACCUCCACCUUCCAGGUUCAAGCGAUUCUUGUGCCUCAGACUCCCAAGUAGCUAGGAUUACAGGAAAUUCUGAAACAGCCACACCUACAAAUGUAGACUUGCCUCAGGUCAUCCCCAAGUCUGAGAACAGCAGCCAGCCAGCCAAGAAAGCCAAGGGGGCUGCAAAGACAAAGCAGCAGCUGCAGAAACAGCAACAUCCCAAGAAGGCCUCCUUCCAGAAGCUGAAUGGCAUCUCCAAAGGGGCAGACUCAGAAUUGUCCACUGUACCUUCUGUCACAAAGACCCAAGCUUCCUCCAGCUUCCAGGAUAGCAGUCAGCCAGCUGGAAAAGCCGAAGGGAUCAGGGAGCCAAAGGUGACUGGGAAGCUAAAGCAACGAUCACCUAAAUUACAGUCCUCCAAGAAAGUUGCUUUCCUCAGGCAGAAUGCCCCUCCCAAGGGCACAGACACACAAACACCGGCUGUGUUAUCCCCAUCCAAGACUCAGGCCACCCUGAAACCUAAGGACCAUCAUCAGCCCCUUGGAAGGGCCAAGGGGGUUGAGAAGCAGCAGUUGCCAGAGCAGCCUUUUGAGAAAGCUGCCUUCCAGAAACAGAAUGAUACCCCCAAGGGGCCUCAGCCUCCCACUGUGUCUCCCAUCCGUUCCAGCCGCCCCCCACCAGCAAAGAGGAAGAAAUCUCAGUCCAGGGGCAACAGCCAGCUGCUGCUAUCUUAGAUGGUUGAAAACUAGACGGGUGGCUCACUGCCAUUGUCACCAGGUUGGAACUCUUGCCUCUGUGAGGAUGCCUUCUCUACUGUGCAUACCCAUGAAAUUUAAUACACAUUUUAAAACCUCUG